AGAACUGCUCCCGGCCCGGAUCGCUAUGGCAGCGGCGUCGUCGCGGGCCGGGCCCCAGCAAUCCCGCCCGGGCCCGGCUGCCUCAACAGCCGCCCCCACUGCCCCCUCUCGGGCAUGAACCGAGCUUCUUGUUGCCGCCCGCUGCCCUACCCGCCGCUGCCGCCGCAUCCCGACUCUGGGCCAGCGCUGGGAACAUGCCCCUGGCCGCCUACUGCUACCUGCGGGUCGUGGGCAAGGGGAGCUAUGGAGAGGUGACGCUUGUGAAGCACCGGCGGGACGGCAAGCAGUAUGUCAUCAAAAAACUGAACCUCCGAAAUGCCUCUAGCCGAGAGCGGCGAGCUGCUGAACAGGAAGCCCAGCUCUUGUCUCAGUUGAAGCAUCCCAACAUUGUCACCUACAAGGAGUCAUGGGAAGGAGGAGAUGGUCUGCUCUACAUUGUCAUGGGCUUCUGUGAAGGAGGUGAUUUGUACCGAAAGCUCAAGGAGCAGAAAGGGCAGCUUCUGCCUGAGAAUCAGGUGGUAGAGUGGUUUGUACAGAUCGCCAUGGCUUUGCAGUAUUUACAUGAAAAACACAUCCUUCAUCGAGAUCUGAAAACUCAAAAUGUCUUCCUAACAAGAACAAACAUCAUCAAAGUAGGGGACCUAGGAAUUGCCCGAGUGUUAGAGAACCACUGUGACAUGGCUAGCACCCUCAUUGGCACACCCUACUACAUGAGCCCUGAAUUGUUCUCAAACAAACCCUACAACUAUAAGUCUGAUGUUUGGGCUCUAGGAUGCUGUGUCUAUGAAAUGGCCACCUUGAAGCAUGCUUUCAAUGCAAAAGAUAUGAAUUCUUUAGUUUAUCGGAUUAUUGAAGGAAAGCUGCCACCAAUGCCAAGAGAUUACAGCCCAGAGCUGGCAGAACUGAUAAGAACAAUGCUGAGCAAAAGGCCUGAAGAAAGGCCGUCUGUGAGGAGCAUCCUGAGGCAGCCUUAUAUAAAGCGGCAAAUCUCCUUCUUUUUGGAGGCCACAAAGAUAAAAACCUCCAAAAAUAACAUUAAAAAUGGUGACUCUCAAUCCAAGCCUUUUGCUACAGUGGUUUCUGGAGAGGCAGAAUCAAAUCAUGAAGUAAUCCACCCCCAACCACUCUCUUCUGAGGGCUCCCAGACAUAUAUAAUGGGUGAAGGCAAAUGUUUGUCCCAGGAGAAACCCAGGGCCUCUGGUCUCUUGAAGUCACCUGCCAGUCUGAAAGCCCAUACCUGCAAACAGGACUUGAGCAAUACCACAGAACUAGCCACAAUCAGUAGCGUAAAUAUUGACAUCUUACCUGCAAAAGGGAGGGAUUCAGUGAGUGAUGGCUUUGUUCAGGAGAAUCAGCCAAGAUAUUUGGAUGCCUCUAAUGAGUUAGGAGGUAUAUGCAGUAUUUCUCAAGUGGAAGAGGAGAUGCUGCAGGACAACACUAAAUCCAGUGCCCAGCCUGAAAACCUGAUUCCCAUGUGGUCCUCUGACAUUGUCACUGGGGAAAAGAAUGAACCAGUGAAGCCUCUGCAGCCCCUAAUCAAAGAACAAAAGCCAAAGGACCAGAGUCUUGCCCUGUCGCCCAAGCUGGAGUGCAGUGGCACAAUCUUGGCUCACAGCAACCUCCGCCUCCUGGGUUCAAGUGAUUCUCCAGCCUCAGCCUCCCGAGUAGCUGGGAUUACAGGCGUGUGCCACCACGCCCAGGAUCAAGUUGCUGGUGAAUGUAUUAUAGAAAAACAGGGCAGAAUCCACCCAGAUUUACAGCCACACAACUCUGGGUCUGAACCUUCCCUGUCUCGACAGCGACGGCAAAAGAGGAGAGAACAGACUGAGCACAGAGGGGAAAAGAGACAGGUCCGCAGAGAUCUCUUUGCUUUCCAAGAGUCGCCUCCUCGAUUUUUGCCUUCUCAUCCCAUUGUUGGGAAAGUGGAUGUCACAUCAACACAAAAAGAGGCUGAAAACCAACGUAGAGUGGUCACUGGGUCUGUGAGCAGUUCAAGGAGCAGUGAGAUGUCAUCAUCAAAGGAUCGACCAUUAUCAGCCAGAGAGAGGAGGCGACUAAAGCAGUCACAGGAAGAAAUGUCCUCUUCAGGCCCUUCAGUGAGGAAAGCGUCUCUGAGUGUAGCAGGGCCAGGAAAACCCCAGGAAGAAGACCAGCCCUUGCCUGCCCGACGGCUCUCCUCUGACUGCAGCGUCACUCAGGAAAGGAAACAGAUUCAUUGUCUGUCUGAGGAUGAGUUAAGUUCUUCUACAAGUUCAACUGAUAAGUCAGAUGGGGAUUACGGGGAAGGGAAAGGUCAGACAAAUGAAAUUAAUGCCUUGGUACAAUUGAUGACUCAGACCCUGAAACUGGAUUCUAAAGAGAGCUGUGAAGAUGUCCCGGUAGCAAACCCAGUGUCAGAAUUCAAACUUCAUCGGAAAUAUCGGGACACACUGAUACUUCAUGGGAAGGUUGCAGAAGAGGCAGAGGAAAUCCAUUUUAAAGAGCUACCUUCAGCUAUUAUGCCAGGUUCUGAAAAGAUCAGGAGACUAGUUGAAGUCUUGAGAACUGAUGUAAUUCGUGGCCUGGGAGUUCAGCUUUUAGAGCAGGUGUAUGAUCUUUUGGAGGAGGAGGAUGAAUUUGAUAGAGAGGUACGUUUGCGGGAGCACAUGGGUGAAAAGUAUACAACUUACAGUGUGAAAGCUCGCCAGUUGAAAUUUUUUGAAGAAAACAUGAAUUUUUGAGCAUUUGUCCUAAUCUGCUGCCAGAAUUAAAGACCUAUUUUUAGAGGAUUUUGGCUUAAAAAGCAAGGGCAAACAGUCAUUUGGAAGCCACUCACCACUGUUUUAUAUCUCUUUUUUAUAUCUCUUUGGCGUUUCCCUACAGAAAAGAAAUUGGACAGAACAGAAUAAUAUGAAGCAGGAUCACAAAAGAAAAAAAACUUUGGCUUUCAUAUUCUCUUUGUGAGGACAAAUCUGUUGUUUGUUUGAUUACUGUUUACUGAGCCUUAAUCCACCAAGUUUAUAUUUAGAAUUUUAUUUUUUUAAGGUACUAAUUAACUUAAACACAGAGCUAUAAAAUGCUGGAUUGAAAAUUUUAUAUUGUAAUGUAGAGAUAAAAGCAGUAGGAGAAACAAAUGACAUAAUAUGUCGUCAUAAUUCCUGCUAUUGUUAAUAACCUUAAGGAGUAGUUGAUAAAUUAUAAAAUUUUAAAAAGUCAAUUCAGUUCUAGAAAUAGAUUUAAAGAAUAUGAAGUUCUAUCUAGUACUUGAGCAGCUGUAUUUCUUUUCUACACAUUGAUGGACUUUUAAUAUUUUAUUCUCAUUUAAUAUAAACCUCAUCUAGGGUAUAUACAAAUUAAAACUGAGACACAUUGGCUUUGUAAAUCAGUAUGUUUUUACAUAAUGGUUUUGUUAGAUUUAUUUUUCCAUCAGUGAAAACAUUUCUUAAACACAAAUUUCAUUUCCAUUUAAGCAAUUUGUAAGCAAAGUCCAGGUCCAUUUAGUUUUUGGAUAUAUUUAAUGUUUGUCUCCUGAAGUUUGUCUUCAUGUACUGUAAGAUAUUAGUUGUCUUUCCAUGUUUUAAAUGUAUGAUUAUAUAGCACAUAUUUUAUUAGUUGUUUAAUAAGAGGUAAUACCCAUCUAGGAAAGAAAUUUUAUGAAGUUAAAUACAAGUCUUGAAUAGUACAUUUUCACUUCUGUAUUCGAGGGACUCUAAAAAUAAAUAUUGCUCCAGAAAUGUUUUCAGGUGUUUUUUUUUUGAGACAGAGUUUCACUCUGUCAGUCAGGCUGGAGUGCAGUGGCAUGAUCUCAACUCACUGCAACCUCCACUUCUGGGGCUCAAGUGGUAUUCCUGCCUGAGCCUCCCUAGUAGCUGAGACCACAGGCGUGUGCCACCACACCUGGCUAGUUUUUGUAUUUUUUGUAGAGACAGGGUUACACCACAUUGCCCAGGCUGAUCUCAGAACUCCUGGGCUCAAGCAAUCCACUCACCUCAGCCUCCCAAAGUGCCAGGAUUACAGGAAUGAGCCACUGUGCCCAGCCCUGUUUUCAGUUUCUAUAACUAAAAAUAUAUCUAUCUUUGAAAAUUACACACACACACAAAUACUCUAAUGAAAUGUUCCCUUUACAGCCACUUAACAAUUUUUUUUUUUUUUUAAGACACAGUCUUGCUCUGUCACCCAGGCUGAAGUGCAGUGGCCCAAUCUCAGAUCACUGCAAGCUCCGCCUCCCAGGUUCACUCCAUUCUCCUACCUCAUCCUCUCGAGUAGCUGGGACUACAGUUGCCCGCCACCAUGCCCGGCUAAUUUUUUUGUAUUUUUUUAGUAGAGACAGGGUUUCACCGUGUUAGCCAGGAUGGUCUCAAUCUCCUGACCUCGUGAUCUGCCCGCCUCGGCCUCCCAAAGUGCUGGGAUUACAGGCGUGAGCCACCGCGCCCGGCACACUUAACAGAUUUUUAUUUAGAGUUUACUGUGUGCCAGGUUCUCUGCCAGGAGCUGGGGAUAUAGUGGUGAAUAAAACAAUACUUCCUGCCCUUUUACAGUGCUCACAGCCUGGUUUCUGAUAACUCUUAUUUUCACUUUGAAGGGUUUGCUAGAACUCAACUUGCAAAACCAUCAAGUCCCAAUGCCCAGUUGGGAACAAAUCUUUGGCAAACUUGGUAUCCUUGAGCUAUUCACCUUUCCGUGCAUGUUUUGGAAAUCCACAUCGUUCUGGAGAGUCAUCAGUUUUACUUAAUUUUUCUAAUGUAUUGGUAUAAAGUAGGUAUUUUAUUAGAAUUAAAGGAAUCUCACCCAUAUCUUUUUUUUUUUUUUUUUUUUUUGAGACAGGGUCUUGCUCUGUCACCCAGCCUGGAGUGCAGUGAGGUGAUCAUAGCUCACUGCAGCCUUGACCUCCUGGGCUUAAGUGAUCCUCCCACCUCAGCCCCUCAAGUAGCUAGGACCACAGGCAUGCACCACCACACCUGGCUAAUUUUUAAAAUUUUUUGUGGAGAGGAAGUCUGUGUUGCCCAGGCUGGUCUCAAACUGCAUUCAAGCAGUCCUCCUGCAUCGGCCUCUGAAAGUGCUGGGAUUAUAGGCAUGAACCACCACACCUGACUUCCCCCAUACUUUCUUAUUAAUUACCAUACUGUAUAUUUUUAUUUUGUUUAAACAUCUUUUCUUCCCACUUUUAUCGUUUUUACUUGAGUGCUUAAUUCAUCUUCCUAAAUUAAUUUAAAAACUCAUCUUUAAGACUGUGAAUUUUCUUCCGAAUAUACCUUUGGCCACAGUUCAGAGACUUUGAUGUGUUACUCUUUUGGCAUUGGUUCUAAAAUGUCAAUCAUUCUUUUUUUUUUUUUUUUGAGAUGGAGUCUUCUUGUUGCCCAGGCUGGAGUACAGUGGUGCGAUCUUGGCUCACUGCAGCCUACGCCUCCUGGGUUCAAGUUCCCCUCCCUCAGCCUCCCGAGUAGCUGGGAUUACAGGCACACACCACCAUGCCUGGCUGAUUUUCGUUAUUUUUAGUAGAGAUGGAGUUUCACCAUGUUGGCCAGGCUGGUCUUGAACUCCUGACCUCAGGUGAUCUGCCUGCCUUGGCCUCCCUAAAUGCUGGGAUUACAGGCUUGAGGCACCAUGCCUGGCCUAAAGUGUCAGUAAUUCUGAUUUCGGUUUUCUCUUUUAGAAGUUUUGAUUUCCACAGACUUACAAAGCUAAGGAAGUUUUAUGUCCUUGCUCUGGCUACACUGCAGUGUUACUGAAUAUCACCUGCACAACCUUUACUGCUUGCAGUUUUUUUUUUCCUGUUGCUUUGUACAUGAUCCGUUAUUCAAAUGGCCUUAUAGGCAUUCAAUAAAGGUGAAAUGUUAAAUACAAAAUCACUUGUCUAUUAAAUUUUAUUCAAGGUUCUAUAUAAGAUCUGAUAAAUGGAACUUUGUGAUGGAAAUGUUUUAUAUGGUAGCCACUAGUCACAUAUAGCUAUUGAACCUUUGAAUCAUGGCUAGUUUUAGAGUUUUAUAUUUUAAUUUUAAUUAAAUAGACGUGUCUAGUGGCACCAUAUUGUACAAUGCAGUUCUCAUUCAAUAAAUCUUAAGUACUUAACAAUG